ACCGGUCCUCUUCACUACUUUGCCCAGAUUAUUCCCUCCCUUGUCGCGGGCUGACCUUCUUUUCCUCCAUUCCUUCCCCCCGAAAUUAACCUCUUCCCAGUUCCAGACCAAUCCUUUCCAUGUCCCUAAUUCAUUUCCUUACCAGGCUAACUCUCAAAUUAACAGAAACCUCUCUACCCCGGCCUAAUUCCUGCAUUGCCUCAGACCAGCCCUUCUCAAAUUACCUCCUUCCCUGUACCAAGCUGAGCCUUCCCUUGCUCUCUAGACGAAUCCUCCUACCUUUCCAGGCUAAACUUCUACCUGCCUCAUGCAAACUUAUCCCAAUCUAACGAUUCCUUCAUUUCAUUGUAACUCCCGUUUCCCCCAAAGUCCGAAAUCCAGCCAGGCUCCUUUCAAAGUCCUUACUCAAUUUCUGUGCUUUCCCACAACCUUCAAAGUAAUCCGACGUCGGGUGAGGUGUGAUUGGAAGCGUGGCUCCAACACCACUGGCCAAGAAUUGGUAAUUGUGGAAGCCAGAUGGAGAUGAUUGGUAUAUGGAGGCUGCAUAGAGCCUGGACCUGGGCACUGGGGUGAGCUGAGCCGGACACCAGUCCCAUCUAAACCCCAGGACAAAGUGGAAGCAGCUGAGGCAACACCAGUGGCCCUGGACAGUGACACCUCCGGGGCUGAAAAUGCAGCAGUGAGUGCUAUGCUGCACGCUGUAGCCGCCAGCCGCCUGCCUGUUUGCAGCCAGCAGCAGGGUGAACCCGACUUGACAGAGCAUGAGAAAGUGGCCAUCCUGGCCCAGCUGUACCACGAGAAGCCACUGGUGUUCCUGGAGCGCUUCCGCACAGGCCUCCGUGAGGAGCAUCUGGCCUGCUUUGGCCACGUGCGUGGCGACCACCGUGCAGACUUCUACUGUGCUGAGGUGGCCCGGCAGGGCACUGCCCGGCCCCGCACCCUGCGUACCCGCCUGCGUAACCGGCGCUAUGCUGCCCUGCGAGAGCUGAUCCAAGGGGGCGAGUACUUCAGUGAUGAGCAGAUGCGGUUCCGGGCCCCCCUGCUAUAUGAGCAGUACAUCGGGCAGUAUCUCACCCAGGAGGAGCUCAGUGCCCGCACCCCAACCCACCAGCCCCCCAAGCCCGGGUCCCCCGGGAGACCUGCUUGCCCGCUCUCCAACUUGCUGCUCCAGUCCUACGAGGAGCGGGAGCUACAGCAGCGUCUGCUCCAACAGCAGGAGGAGGAGGAGGCCUGCUUGGAGGAAGAGGAAGAGGAGGAGGACAGUGACGAGGAAGACCAGAGGUCAGGCAAGGACUCGGAGGCCUGGGUUCCCGACUCGGAGGAGAGGCUGAUCCUGCGAGAGGAGUUCACCAGCCGCAUGCACCAGCGCUUCCUAGAUGGCAAGGACGGGGACUUUGACUACAGCACAGUAGACGACAACCCCGACUUCGACAACCUCGACAUCGUGGCACGGGAUGAGGAGGAGAGGUACUUUGAUGAGGAAGAACCUGAGGAUGCGCCCAGCCCAGAGCUGGAUGGGGACUGAUGGCCGCCACCCUUCCCACCGCCUGCCCCAUCCCCAUCCCCAACAAGGCAGCUGAUUCCAGGCCUGCUCAGUGACCCUUUCUCUAGGGGGACAUCAGGGCAGUGCCCCACAACCCACACACACCACCAUCUCACUGGGUCUAGUCUCAUCUCAGACAACCCCCACCCCCACUGUUUCUGGGGUUCCCUUUCUCAUCUCUCCCACCCUGUCUCCUGCCUCUGUCUUUCUUGGUGUCUGUCUGGGCUUCUUUCUGUCUCUUUCUGUCUUUCUGUCUCUCUCCCUACCCCCGCUCCCUCUUUCCAGUGCUCUGGCUGGCUGUCUCUCCCUUUCUCCCCCUCUCUCUCUGCCUUAGGCUCUGUCUCCACCGCAGGGCCCAAGGUGAAAGUCCUCCCCUUGCCGGAGGCCAGCUGGCAGGGCCUUUCGUGGCUGGAAGUGGCCAGUUUGGUUCCGGUGCUGACCCCUAGGCCCCAGCGCAGCUGCCUCCCGUGCUGUCUGUCUCCCCCUCUCUGUUUAUGUCUGCGCUGUGUCUCACACUCAGAGCCUCCUUGCUUCUGUUAGGUUCCCAUCUCUCCUUCUGCCUCACUCUGGGCCUCUUCUUUCUACUUGUACAUUUCCACCUCUCUAGGCCUCUGCUCUCACUGUCCCUCUCUGUCUGUCUCUCAGCCUUUAUCUCUGGGUUUUGAUCCCCCACUCCAGGCUCUGGGCCCCUUCUUCCCCCUUCCCUCAAACCUGGCUGCUAUAGGCAGCAGAACCCUGACCACUGAGUAAUACAGCCCCAGGGGAGGGAGGAGACCCCAGGCAGGGAGGAUGGGGGCAGCUCUCUUCUCUCCCCAGGACCCAGGCUGUGGAUCACGGGGCCUGCCAGCUUGAGUGUAGAGGGAGGGGGGACUCUACCCUUCUCAGCCCCACCAGCCCCCCUCUGCCCAACCACAAUUUUCCCUUCCUCCGCCUUCCUCUCCCUCUCCUGUUUACACUCCCCAAAUGCGCACAGGCUGUUAUCAUGGGUCCUGAGUCAUCCCACACACAGCCUGCCCCAGCGUCCCUGCCCCCAGCUGGCCGCAGGGCCCGCCCCAUGGAGCCCCCUGCCGCCCUGGGCUAAUGGGAGCCAGAUGGCCGCCUGGUGACUCAGCCACCGGGCCUGUGGGAACCCAGGCGUCCCGCCUUCCCAUGCCCCCACACCCGGCUCCUGCUCCCCCAGCAGACACACACAGGAGGGCCUGGCCACUGUUGAGGGGGCACACAGGGCAAGGGUCACCAAGUCGGGGCCUAGGGACUCCUCAUGCCUCUGAGAUGGAAUGGUGGUAUCCUGCCGUGGCCAAGCCUGAAGGACCCUCAAAACUGCCUCCUGGAGUCCACGGUUCCUGACCUCCGAGCCUCAGCUAUGCCCUCUGGGUCAACCAGAAUUAGAGCCAGACAGGGAAAGUGAGAGCUGGAUGGAGGCAGACAAGAUGCUCAGAGCGACUAUUAAAGAACGAAAGCCUCUGCUACGGAGCGCUUCUGUCCUCUGUCAGGCCCGAGCGAAGUGCCUGACACCGGGUUGGAUCCUCAGAUGGCCCCAUGAACUAGUGAAGUGGGUCAAAGGAGGCCUGGAAAGAUGUUGCUUCCUCAAGGCCACUCGGCCAUCAGAGGCAGAAAUGAAACAGGAACCCAGGCCUAGAAUCACAAAGGUCCUAGAAACCACUUGGCUGUCUGGCCUCUCAGGUGUCAGGGCCAUCCAGAGUGAGACAGCAUUGGAGGGACAAGUGUGCAUGCAGAUGUCCUCAGACGGGAAGGUUUGAGAAGGGUCAGAUGGUAGGCGGGCCUAACAAGGGCUCCGUGCUAGCCACUGUCCCGCACACAGACAGGAUCAGGUCAUCUUGAUAUGGAGAUCAGUCCCCAAAUCACUGAAUUGUCCCAGCAGUGCUAUGCCCUAGGUACUACCAAUAUCACUCCUCUAUUUCCCAGAGGAGGAAGCAGCAGCUAGACUCCAGGACCUUGGGGUCAUAUCUCUCAGAAAGCCAAGAGUGCAGGAUGAGAGCUGUCUGUCUCUUACCUGCCUGUAUUUGUGCCCCAUUUUUAAAGAGCAGAGGGCCUGGGCCACAGGAAAGGUAUCAGCCCUUGGUGAUAGGCACAUUUUUUACCAGUCUAUCAUUUGGUCAUUAAAUUUGUUUACAAUAUA